AGUCGCCAUCACCGCCAGACCGCAGAGACAGGUUCGGAUCCGCGGUCCUCUUGCCUCUUUCCAGGCCUCGAUGAGUGUUAAAUCGCCAUUUAAUGUGAUGUCAAGAAAUAAUUUGGAAGCACCUCCUUGUAAGAUGACAGAGCCAUUUAAUUUUGAGAAAAAUGAAAACAAGCUUCCACCACAUGAGUCUUUAAGAAGUCCUGGAACACUUCCUAACCACCCUAAUUUCAGGCUGAAAAGCUCAGAGAAUGGAAAUAAAAAGAACAAUUUUUUGCUUUGUGAGCAAACCAAACAAUAUUUGGCUAGUCAGGAAGACAAUUCAGUUUCUUCAAACCCGAAUGGCAUCAACGGAGAAGUAGUUGGCUCCAAAGGAGACAGGAAAAAAUUGCCAGCAGGAAACUCAGUGUCACCACCAAGUGCUGAAAGUAAUUCACCACCCAAAGAAGUGAAUAUUAAGCCUGGAAAUAAUGUACGUCCUGCAAAAUCAAAAAAACUAAACAAGUUGGUCGAGAAUUCCUUGUCCAUAAGUAAUCCAGGGCUCUUCACCUCCUUAGGACCUCCUCUUCGGUCCACAACUUGCCAUCGCUGUGGCCUAUUUGGAUCGCUGAGGUGCUCUCAGUGCAAGCAGACCUACUAUUGCUCCACAGCAUGUCAAAGAAGAGACUGGUCUGCACACAGCAUCGUGUGCAGGCCUGUUCAGCCAAAUUUCCACAAACUUGAAAAUAAAUCAUCUAUUGAAACAAAGGAUGUGGAGGUAAACAAUAAGAGUGACUGUCCACUUGGAGUUACUAAGGAAAUAGCCAUUUGGGCUGAGAGAAUAAUGUUUUCUGAUUUGAGAAGUCUACAACUCAAGAAAACCAUGGAAAUAAAGGGUACGGUUACCGAAUUCAAACACCCAGGGGACUUCUACGUGCAGUUAUAUUCUUCAGAAGUUUUAGAAUACAUGAACCAACUCUCUGCCAGCUUAAAAGAAACAUAUGCAAAUGUGCAUGAAAAAGACUAUAUUCCUGUUAAGGGGGAAGUUUGUAUUGCCAAGUACACUGUUGAUCAGACCUGGAACAGAGCAAUCAUACAAAACGUUGAUGUGCAGCAAAAGAAGGCACAUGUCUUAUAUAUUGAUUAUGGAAAUGAAGAAAUAAUUCCAUUAAACAGAAUUUACCACCUCAACAGGAACAUUGACUUGUUUCCUCCUUGUGCCAUAAAGUGCUUUGUAGCCAAUGUUAUCCCAGCAGAAGGGAAUUGGAGCAGUGAUUGUAUCAAAGCUACUAAACCACUGUUAAUGGAGCAGUACUGCUCCAUAAAGAUUGUCGACAUCUUGGAAGAGGAAGUGGUUACCUUUGCUGUAGAAGUUGAGCUGCCAAAUUCAGGAAAACUUUUAGACCAUGUGCUUAUAGAAAUGGGAUAUGGCUUGAAACCCAGUGGACAAGAUUCUAAGAAGGAAAAUGCAGAUCAAAGUGAUCCUGAAGAUGUUGGAAAAAUGACAACUGAAAACAACAUUGUCGUAGACAAAAGUGACCUAAUCCCAAAAGUGUUAACUUUGAAUGUAGGUGAUGAGUUUUGUGGUGUGGUUGCCCACAUUCAAACACCAGAAGACUUCUUUUGUCAACAACUGCAAAGUGGCCGAAAGCUUGCUGAACUUCAGGCAUCCCUUAGCAAGUACUGUGAUCAGUUGCCUCCACGCUCUGAUUUUUAUCCAGCCAUUGGUGAUAUAUGUUGUGCUCAGUUCUCAGAGGAUGAUCAGUGGUACCGUGCCUCUGUUUUGGCUUACGCUUCUGAAGAAUCUGUACUGGUCGGAUAUGUAGAUUAUGGAAACUUUGAAAUCCUUAGUUUGAUGAGACUUUGUCCCAUAAUCCCAAAGUUGUUGGAAUUGCCAAUGCAAGCUAUAAAGUGUGUACUAGCAGGAGUAAAGCCAUCAUUAGGAAUUUGGACUCCAGAAGCUAUUUGUCUCAUGAAAAAACUUGUACAGAACAAAAUAAUCACAGUGAAAGUGGUGGACAAGUUGGAAAACAGUUCCCUGGUGGAGCUUAUUGAUAAAUCCGAGACGCCUCAUGUCAGUGUUAGCAAAGUUCUCCUAGAUGCAGGCUUUGCUGUGGGAGAACAGAGUAUGGUGACAGAUAAACCCAGUGACGUGAAAGAAACCAGUGUUCCCUUGGGUGUGGAAGGAAAAGUAAAUCCAUUGGAGUGGACAUGGGUUGAACUUGGUGUUGACCAAACAGUAGAUGUUGUGGUCUGUGUGAUAUAUAGUCCUGGAGAAUUUUAUUGCCAUGUGCUUAAAGAGGAUGCUUUAAAGAAACUCAAUGAUUUGAACAAGUCAUUAGCAGAACACUGCCAGCAGAAGUUACCUAAUGGUUUCAAGGCAGAGAUAGGACAACCUUGUUGUGCUUUUUUUGCAGGUGAUGGUAGUUGGUAUCGUGCUUUAGUCAAGGAAAUCUUACCAAAUGGACAUGUUAAAGUACAUUUUGUGGAUUAUGGAAACAUCGAAGAAGUUACUGCAGAUGAACUCCGAAUGAUAUCAUCAACAUUUUUAAACCUUCCCUUUCAGGGAAUACGGUGCCAGUUAGCAGAUAUACAGUCUAGAAACAAACAUUGGUCUGAAGAAGCCAUAACAAGAUUCCAGAUGUGUGUUGCUGGGAUAAAAUUGCAAGCCAGAGUGGUUGAAGUCACUGAAAAUGGGAUAGGAGUUGAACUCACCGAUCUCUCCACUUGUUAUCCCAGAAUAAUUAGUGAUGUUCUGAUUGAUGAACAUCUGGUUUUAAAAUCUGCUUCACCACAUAAAGACUUACCAAAUGACAGACUUGUUAAUAAACAUGAGCUUCAAGUUCAUGUACAGGGACUUCAAGCUACCUCUUCAGCUGAGCAAUGGAAGACGAUAGAAUUGCCAGUGGAUAAAACUAUACAAGCAAAUGUAUUAGAAAUCAUAAGCCCAAACUUGUUUUAUGCUCUACCAAAAGGGAUGCCAGAAAAUCAGGAAAAGCUGUGCAUGUUGACAGCUGAAUUAUUAGAAUACUGCAAUGCUCCGAAAAGUCGACCACCCUAUAGACCAAGAAUUGGAGACGCAUGCUGUGCCAAAUACACAAGUGAUGAUUUUUGGUAUCGUGCAGUUGUUCUGGGGACAUCAGACACUGAUGUGGAAGUGCUCUAUGCAGACUAUGGAAACAUUGAAACCCUGCCUCUUUGCAGAGUGCAACCAAUCACCUCUAGCCACCUGGCGCUUCCUUUCCAAAUUAUUAGAUGUUCACUUGAAGGAUUAAUGGAAUUGAAUGGAAGCUCUUCUCAAUUAAUAAUAAUGCUAUUAAAAAAUUUCAUGUUGAAUCAGAAUGUAAUGCUUUCUGUGAAAGGAAUUACAAAGAAUGUCCAUACAGUGUCAGUUGAGAAAUGUUCUGAGAAUGGGACUGUCGAUGUAGCUGAUAAGCUAGUGACAUUUGGUCUGGCAAAAAACAUCACACCUCAAAGGCAGAGUGCUUUAAAUACAGAAAAGAUGUAUAGGAUGAAUUGCUGCUGCACAGAGUUACAGAAACAAGUUGAAAAACAUGAACAUAUUCUUCUCUUCCUCUUAAACAAUUCAACCAAUCAAAAUAAAUUUAUUGAAAUGAAAAAACUGUUAAAAAGUUAAGUAAGUUAAAUCGUAUGUUUUCGCCUCUUCUGUGAUCACCAAUAGGACAUCUUCAGGCAUAUUGGCAGGAUAGAGCUAAUGGAGUGAAACCUAUUGUAAGGCUGUACUUUCGUGAUUUAAUGACCUGAGGUUUGGUCAUAAUGCUUCUGCUGUUUUUGUAGGUUUAUCUGAUCGUUUUCCUUUGCUACUGCUAAUGGAACUGAACCCCCAGGGGUAUUCCAGUUGUAAUAGCCUUUCCUUACUGUUGUUUGGUUCUGUGAAUGCCUAUGUUAUUGAUAUGUGGAGGGACUUGUAAAACUUGUUGUGACAUAAAGCUUAGCCUCAGAUUUUUUGUCUAGAUCUGAAAUUAACUCAGAGCUCACUUAUGCACAUUGCUGUAAAUAUGUUUAGCACUUUUUGCGAGGGGUAUCUAAAGGGCCAAGAACGGAAAGUGGAUCUAAAGGGCCAAGAACGGAAAGUGGGCUGCACUGAGGGUAUUUUUCAUUUAAAAACAAAACAUACUCCCUGCUUUUGGCUGUGGUGAUUCUAGUGUCUAAAGAACAUACUGGUGAGUUUUAAACCAGUGUUCCUCCCCACCCCACCCCCAUAUUUUAAAUGUCUGGGAUCCUUUGUUGUAAGAUGGUUCUCAGAAAUAAAUUUUUGAUUAAGAGCCAAUUAGAACUUCUGAUCAGGGCUGGGGGUGGUGGCUCACGCCUGUAAUCCCAGCACUUUGGGAGGCUGAGGCGGGCAGAUCACCUGAGCCCAGGCGUUCGAAGUCAGCCUGGCCAAGAUGGCGAAACACUGCCUCUACUUAAAAUACAAAAUUAGCUGGGCAUGGUGGUGCACACCUGUUAACCCAGCUACUUGGGAGGCUGAGACAGGAGAAUCGCUUGAAUCCAGGAGGCGGCGGUUGCAGUGAGCCAAGACUGCUAUUAUACUCCAGCCUGGGUGACAGAGUGAGAGUUUGUCUCAAAAACAAAACAAAACAAAACAAAAAAAAAAACAACCUCUAAUCUCAGAAUAAAGUUGUCUCUCCUCACCACUUUGAGUUGUUACAGUUCCAGCCAAAAGCAAAGGAACUUUGAUUUACUUAAUAUGUGCACUUUUGUUGGUUAACAAAUUUAUAUUAAACUGUUUGGAAAUAGUUCAAGAGGUGGCUAUAAUACUCUUCAUGAAUCUUUUAUGGGUGUAGUAACUCUCAAGUAGGAACCAACUGCCAACUGUGUUAAAACAUAUCUUUCAUGUGGUAAUAGACCGUUUCUUUGCGUUUUAAGAAAGGUCAAUUGAAUUAUAAGCUAAAUGUAAUUAAUGCAAGAUCAACUAUCUUGACUCUCAUGUUUCCUUUUACAAAUUUUGGGUUAUUACAACUUUCAGUCCUUUCUAAUACAUUGUCUUAAUACUGACUGUUUUGUAUGUUUAAGCUUAAAAUCUUUUAAUCUUUUUUUUUUUUUUUUUUGGAGACGGAGUCUUGCUCUGUCACCCAGGCUGGAGUGCAAUGGCGUGAUCUCGGCUCACUGCAAGCUCCACCUCCCAGGUUCACGCAAUUCUCCCACAUCAGCCUCCCAAGUAGCUGGGACUACAGGCGCACACUGCCACACCCGGCUAAUCUUAAACUUAAUGGUGAUUUUAAUUUCAUAGAUCAAGGAACAUGCAAUGACAUGGAUUUCUGGAAUUUAGUCCUAGUAUCAAGUCACUAUAUAUAUAUAUAUUUUUUUUUUAUUUUUUAUUUUUAUUUUUUUUUGAGACAGUCUCGCUCUGUUGUCCAGGCUGGAGUGCAGUGGCGCUAUCUCAGCUCACUACAACCUCCGCCUCCCGGGUUCAUGCCAUUCUCCUGCCUCAGCUUCCCAAGUAGCUGGGACUAUAGGUGCCCGCCACCACACCCAGCUAAUCUUUUUGUAUUUUUAGUAGAGACAGGGUUUCACCGUGUUAGCCAGGAUGGUCUCGAUCUCCUGACCUCGUGAUCUGCCCUCCUCGGCCUCCCAAAGUGCUGGGAUUACAGGCGUGAGCCACUGCGCCCGGCCACCAAGUCAUUACAUUUUUAACCAAGUUGGUUGGCCUGUAUGUUCUUCUUAUCUGUGUAACAGGCAUUUUUCCUAAGGAUAUUGAGUGUGCUUACACAUAAAACUUAAAGUGAAAUUUCAUUGUUUCUUGAUAGAUUUAAGACAGGGCUUAGUAGCUUUCAAAAGAAAACUUGAUUUAAAGCAUAGUAGUUGAACUGGAUUUUUCCUGACUGUGGGAAUAAAUAGAUAUUUUAUUUACAUUUGAAUACAGUGCAAUACCUUGUGUUUGGGUAGUACGUAUUUACAAAGCAUUUUUACAUCUACUCACAUACUUAAUCUUCACAAUGCCCUUGAAAAGAAAGUAGGACCCAUUUUACAGUUAAGGAAGCUGAGGCUCAGAGAGGGUUACAUGACUGUCCAAAAUCACAUACAGGCUGAAACACUAGGUCUUACGACUUAAAACAGUUGUGUCAACUUCCCUGAGCUGCUACGUGUACAGUAUCCUUUUAGAUCAGAUCAGUUACAUAGGGCAUGAAACUAGAGGGUUACAUUAUUAGGAAAAAAUAAUGUACAUGAUUGCUUAAGCAUUACUUCAUUGUGGUGAAAAUAGAGCUGAAUAUUUACUCCUUUAAAUUAUUCUUUGAGAUAGAAUGGGUGUAAAAAUGUAUUUUGGCUGGGCAUGGUGGCUCAGGCCUGUAAUCCCAGCACUUUUGGGAGGCUGAGGAGGGCAGGUCACAUGAGGCCCAGGAGUUUGAGACCAUCCUGGCCAACAUGGUGAAACUUUGUCUCUACCAAAAAAAAUAUAGAAUUAGCCAGGUGAGGUGGCGUGCACCUGUAGUCCCAGCUACUGGGGAGGCUGAGGCAGGAGAAUUGCUUGAACCCAGGAGCCGAAGGUUGCAGUGAGCCGAGAUGGCACCACUGCACUCCAGCUUGGGCAACAGAGUGAGACCCUGUCUCAAAAAAAUAAAAUAAAAGACAAACACAUGUAUUUCAUCAUCUGGAGAAAUUUAAUUGUUAGCAAUUUAAUUGUAAAAUUGCUAAAACAGAAGUGCUGUGGUGAUAUGAACAUAAAACCCUCUGUAAUCUGUUGCUCAGGUGAUGUUUCAACACACAAGUUAAUGUCAGAUAUCUUUUAUAUAUAAGGAGAGUGCAAACAACUAUAUGUUAUAUUUGUGAAGGGGAGUAUAAACAGCUGUACUUAGCAUAUAUUAUGCUAUGUUAUGGUGGUCAUUAAUUUUCUUAACUGACAGGUCUGGCUUAAAUGCGUAAUUUCAGUUAAAAGUGAAUAUUUUGUUUGCUUGUAUUUGAAAUUAAAAGCCAUAGCAAUUGAGUUUUUGUGUAAGGCAUAAUGAUAGUUGAUUUUUUUUCUUUUUCAGAAACAGCAUCUCUUGGAGGUAAACCCUUAUGAGACAGGAAACAGCAAAGGCUAGCUUUAGGAGAGAAAGUACAGCACCUGGUGUUUUUAUUUAUGAGAACCUUUUCUUUGUCCACUUUCUCUGUAAUGACCUUCUAUCCCUCCGUUUUUGCCUGCCUGCCAUUCUCCUAUUAGGUUGGUGGUUUUUAUUUUCCUCUAAGUUCCUUCCACCAAAUAAAUAUUACGUAAAAAAUUCAUACCAAAUCAAUGAGAAUACUGGCAAGGAAUACAUAGGGACUUUCUGCUAUAUAUGUAACUUUUUAUUACUUAAAGGUACCGAAGGAAGGCCAGGUGCAGUGGCUCACGCCCAGCACUUUGGGAGGCUGAGGUGGGAGGAUCCCUUGAGGCCAGGAGUUCAAGGUUACAGUGAGCUAUGAUAGUGCCACUGCACUCCAGCCUGGGUGACAGAUUUUGUCUUAAAAAAAAAAAAAAAAAAGUUGAUAUGAGUUUUAUUUUCUGUCCGUUUGAAAUAUUUUGUAAUAUUCCCUGCAUUCUCUGUCGUCUGCCUCUUCCACAUAAUGUCCUUUGCUUUCAUGUUUGUUAUCUUCUUUUUCUGUUCACUCAGAGGUCAUCAAUUUCUUUCUCUCCGUCCUUAAUUGGAUUAUUUUUCUUUUGGCCUUUGGGCACAGAGUCUGACCUCUGGACCACUCUAACUGGAGAAGGAACUUUAUGUUCCCUCUCCUGCUGUGUCCACAACCUUAGAAAUCUGUAGCUAGAUUUUUGUUGUUAUAGAUAGAAUUUACUGUUUCUGAAACCCAAAUACAGUUAUCAGUUUAAGGUUAAAAAAAAAAAAAAAACGAAGAGUGUAUAUUUUUCCUGAAGCAUGAAAAUAAUCUCAAAUUCUCCUAAACCACGCAUAUGCAGAAUUAUGGGCUGGCUGACUUUCCUGCCAACCCCAAAGUUUGAAUUUUUUUCAUGAUUUAACUGUCAGACUAUGAAACCUAAGAUGUUUCUCACCAACUCAGCAGAUACUUGAAAGACUUUUUUUUUUUUUUUUUUUUUUUUUGCUUUUACUGGCAAUGUACGUUGUCUAAUCUGUUAAAUGGGAUAUUUCCUCAUGUAAAAAGUUGUUAAAACACUGAUGUGCUUCUGUUAGAUAAAAGCUCACGCUGCUUUGCCCAAUAAAAUUAUUUCACUUCCCAA